GUAAUCCCAGCUACUCGGGAAGCUGAGGCAGGAGAAUCACUUGAACCCGGGAGGCAGAGGUUGCAGGGAGCCAAGAUCUCGCCACUGCACUCCAGCCUGGGUGACAGAGUGAGACUGUGUCUCAGAAAACAAAAAAGACAAAAGUCACAGAGCCCCGCCCAGUCCCAGGCAGGACAGUAACAGGAGGAGGAGGCUGUGGCAGGGAGUGGUUCCGGUGAGUCAGACUUCUGGACCCAGGUUCGAUUGCAUGCCAUAAGACCCACCAAUGUGUGAGCUUGAGUAACGUUCCCUGAGCCCUUCUGCCUCAGUAUACUCAUCUGUAAAAUGGGUAUGUUAAUAGUAUCCACCUCCUCCCAGUGUCGUGAGGAUGAAAUGAACUGAUCAUCGAUGUCAGAGCCGUCGAAGCAUGAUGGAAGGCUCACAGAAACGUGCACUGAAUGCCCUGUGCUAUUAUCGCCGUGUUGACGUGUGAUUCCAUCCAGGCUUUUGUCCUCUUCCACCAUAGUCACGCUGCAUAGAUCGUUUUUUCCCUGGCUUUUGCCAGUCAACACCACCGGGAGCACCUUCCAGAUGACAGCAUGCUUUCUGCAAACUACUCCUUUGACGGCACUUACAUGGUGCAGUCCCUACUGGCACCCAGUGAGGCUCCUCCCCUCACCGCCACGAUUUUCAGAAUUAGACCAUCGCUCACAUGGGAGGAUUUUCCUGGAGAAAGUGUUUUCUCUGCACAGAGGCGCAUUUCCUUAGGGGACAUCCCCAGAGGGCAAAGCGGGCUGGGCAAGUCCACGAUGGUGAACACGCUGUUCAAGUCCAAAGUGUGGAAGUCAAACCCACCGGGCUUGGGGGUGCCCACACCCCAGACGCUGCAGCUGCAUUCACUGACCCAUGUCAUAGAGGAGAAGGGUGUGAAGCUGAAGCUGACGGUGACGGACACGCCCGGCUUCGGGGACCAGAUCAACAAUGACAACUGCUGGGACCCCAUCCUGGGCUACAUCAACGAGCAAUACGAGCAGUACCUGCAGGAGGAGAUCCUCAUCACCCGCCAGCGCCACAUCCCAGACACCCGGGUGCACUGCUGCGUGUACUUUGUACCACCCACUGGGCACUGCCUGCGGCCCCUGGACAUUGAGUUCCUGCAGCGGCUGUGCCGGACUGUGAAUGUGGUGCCCGUGAUUGCCAGGGCCGACAGCCUGACCAUGGAGGAGCGAGAGGCCUUCAGGCGCAGGAUCCAGCAGAACCUGAGGACCCACUGCAUCGACGUCUACCCCCAGAUGUGCUUUGACGAGGACAUCAAUGACAAAAUCCUCAACAGCAAGUUACGGGACCGAAUCCCUUUUGCCGUGGUAGGGGCUGACCAAGAGCACCUGGUGAACGGGAGGUGUGUCCUGGGCCGGAAGACCAAGUGGGGCAUCAUUGAAGUGGAGAACAUGGCGCACUGUGAAUUUCCUCUCCUGAGAGACCUGCUUAUCCGCUCCCACCUCCAAGACCUGAAGGACAUAACCCACAACAUCCACUAUGAGAACUACCGCGUCAUCAGACUCAAUGAAAGCCACCUGCUGCCCCGCGGGCCCGGCUGGGUGAACCUGGCCCCGGCCUCCCCAGGACAGCUGACCACCCCCCGGACCUUCAAGGUCUGCAGGGGGGCCCAUGACGAUUCUGAUGAUGAGUUCUGACCACCGGCGGAUCCCGGGGCUGCUGGGCUUCCUGAGUCCCCAGCGGCUCUCAACACACACCUAUGUACCAGAGCAUCUAUUAAAUGUGAGCCUUGCUUUUUAUGAAAAGCUGUGCUUUGAAAACAAAAGGCAUUUUGUAAAUGACUUCUUUGAGCUAUCCACAAAUAAAAAGGCUGGGUGUCACUCUGUUA